CUCAUGAUCCUCCCCCUUUGGCCUCCCAAAGUACUGGGAUUACGGGCGUGAGCCACCGCGCCUGGCCAUGAUUAUAAAUUUCUACCAAUGAUCCAUUUGAUGAUUUUAAACUUCAUAGACACCAGACAAAGCCUCCGUGCAUGCUGUGAUUGCAGGCGCACACUCAUUGAAUCGGUUGUUAGGUUAACAAACGUUAUAGACCCCUGAGUGCUAAGCACUGUCCUCUGUGCUGAGAGUAGAGAAGCAAAAAAUAGACUGAUUUCUUGCUUUCAGAGCAUGUACAUUAUAGUCGGAGAAGAUAAUAAGCAAAGAUACAAAUGAAAUUAUUAUGUCAGGUAUGGAUAAGACUAGGGAGAAAAAUAUAGCUACAUUUUUGCUAAUACUUUCAGGCAUUCUAUGACCUUUAACUACCCUAUGAGAUGAUGACUAGGAUUUUCAUUCCCAUUUUACAGAUGAGGACACUGAGGCAAAUAUAUGUUAAAGAGUUUGCACAGGGACAGACAUGCAAAUGGCAGAGCCGGGGAGUGACCCCCAAGACCCUUCUCUGGGUCAUCGUCCGGUGCUGCCCCUCUUUCAAACGUUUGUAAAGAACCAGUGCAAUGUGGUUACGACGUUUUUUCAUUUAUUCUUUACUUUUACACAUUUCUUCGGUUAUUGCUCUAUGUUGGUGUUGCCUAGGGUUAAUAACUUCCUAGUGUAGUAAUAGUGAAAUUAUUAAACCUGAAAAGGAAAAAGCAGUGUCUUUUCAGACGAGCUGAGUGACAGGGUCUGUUCUUUGAUGCAUGGGUUAUUGAUUAGUGAUACGAGAUUUGAUUAAUUCUCUCAAGAUAAUUUAAAAAUAAACACUUUGUAUCAAGCUUUCUUUUUAUAGUUGAACUUCUUUUGUUAAGUCAAUAGACUUCUAAUGUGCACAUGUUUACCUAAGUUUUAGGUUUCUGCAUGUAUGUACCUCAGGGAAAACACAAAUGGAGAAAGGAAAAACUCACUUGUCAGCGUGGCCCAAGCCCUGCCGUGGGUCCUUUUGUCAGCGUGUGUGGCCCUGGGGUGCUGGCAUUGUGAAAACCUGGGGACUCCGUCCAGGAGGGGCCGUGUGUGCUGUGAAAUCCUCUCAGCUUACGGUGGUUUGAGUGAAUAGGGCUUGCUCUUCUCACUGAACGAGAAAUCCGGCUGUUUGCUGUGGUUUUCUCCCAGUAUCUUUCCGUCCUCCCGUGGCACCAUCCUUAGCUUGUGGGUUUUAUCCUCAUGUUCAUUGCCUUAUAUUUGCAAAAUGGUGGCUGUAUUUCAAGAUAACAUAUCUUCUUUUUAGGUAGGAAAGAAGGGAAAUGGGGCACCACCCCUGAAGAAGCACCGUGGUUCCAUCUCCGGGAAGGAAAGCCUUCAUGGUAUUCCUUCAUUUCCAUCCACCCACUGGAACCGGACCCAAGUUCACCCUCAGAAAGGCUGAGGGAGCAAGUUCUUCAUGAGUUGUUGGACAGCCUUUUGCCACUCCCUUAGGGGAAUGCAGGGGUUCCAUUCGCUGAGAGCAACACACUCUGCCCUCUGCUGAACCAUGGGAGCAGGCCAGGCUCUGCCACAAGGCUGAGAGGGUUUGGUGGGGGUGGGGUGAGUGUGGGGUGGCCCCACUUGCAUUUUGUCAUUGCCAGCUGUGCCAUGCAGAGGGUCUUGGCUGGGGUUUGUUUCUGUCCAUGGUUUCAGGCAUCUGCUGCAGGGCUUACAACUUAGAUAAGGGUGGUUGCCAUAUGAUGUUCUGCAUGAGGUCCACCUUAGGUGCUUAGACAUUUAAAUUCUUAGAUAUGGUGUCCUUCACACUUUAAUUCACCGCUUUAGUGAGGUGUGUGCACCCGCCAAGGCUCACACGUCAGGAACCACACACGUACGUGCUCCUUAAGGCAGCCUUCAGCCUACUUAGCAACCGCUCUCCAAAAAAUCUGUUUUAAUACCUAAAAUCACCAUGGGCGAUUGGAUUUGACACCGUUCUAUACAUAGAUUUUAUGAGGAUUGGAUUUCUCUGAGCAUGGUUCAGUACUGAGGAUACCAAGCUCCUGCUCACUCUCCCUCCUAUGAGAUUCUUCCUCAGGACCCUGCUGCCCCUGGCCCAGAAAUCAUCCACGACUUCAUUGCUUACGGAAAAGCCGAGGUGCAGGCUGGGCUUUCCAGCUCACCUCACAUCCUGGGUCCCACAGCCACAUUUGUCUCCUCCCUGCUCCGAUGCAUGGCACAGGAUGGCACCCCAAGUCUCCACCCUCACCUGGAAGAUCAGCCUCCCCCGCGUGUCACAGCCAGGUCAGGAUGCACACCUGGUGGCCCCUGACCCCGAGGCCUCUCACCUUGCUCCUUGGUAAUAGUGGGCGCACACUGUCAUUGGGGUGCAGGGUAUGGAGAGCUCCUUGGUAAUAAUGGACACGUGCUGUCACUCGGGUGCAGGGUAUGGAGAGCUCCUUGGUAAUAGUGGACACCUGCUGUCACUCGGGUGCAGGGUAUGGAGAGCUCCUUGGUAAUAGUGGACACCUGCUGUCACUCGGGUGCAGGGUAUGGAGAGCUCCUUGGUAAUAGUGGACACAUGCUGUCACUCGGGUUCAGGGUAUGGAGAGCUCCUUGGUAAUAGUGGAUGCGUGCUGUCACUCGGGUGCAGGGUAUGGAGAGCUCCUUGGUAAUAGUGGAUGUGUGCUGUCACUCGGGUGCAGGGUAUGGAGAGCUCCUUGAUAAUAAUGGACACGUGCUGUCACUCGGUGCAGGGUAUGGAGAGCUCCUUGGUAAUAGUGGAUGCGUGCUGUCACUCGGGUGCAGGGUGUGGAGAGCUCCUUGAUAAUAAUGGACACGUGCUGUCACUCGGGUGCAGGGUAUGGAGAGCUCCUUGGUAAGAGUGGACACGUGCUGUCACUCGGGUGCAGGGUAUGGAGAGCUCCUUGGUAAGAGUGGACACGUGCUGUCACUCGGGUGCAGGGUGUGGAGAGCUCCUUGGUAACAGUGGACACGUGCUGUCACUUGGGUGCAGGGUAUGGAGAGCUCCUUGGUAAUAGUGGACACACGCUGUCACUCGGGUGCAGGGUAUGGAGAGCUCCUUGGUAAUAGUGGAUGCGUGCUGUCACUCGGGUGCAGGGUGUGGAGAGCUCCUUGAUAAUAAUGGACACGUGCUGUCACUCGGGUGCAGGGUAUGGAGAGCUCCUUGGUAAGAGUGGACACGUGCUGUCACUCGGGUGCAGGGUAUGGAGAGCUCCUUGGUAAGAGUGGUCACGUGCUGUCACUCGGGUGCAGGGUAUGGAGAGCUGCUUGGUAAUAGUGGACACGUGCUGUCACUCGGGUGCAGGGUAUGGAGAGCUGCUUGGUAAUAGUGGACACGUGCUGUCACUCGGGUGCAGGGUAUGGAGAGCUCCUUGGUAAGAGUGGACACGUGCUGUCACUCGGGUGCAGGGUAUGGAGAGCUGCUUGGUAAUAGUGGACACGUGCUGUCACUCGGGUGCAGGGUAUGGAGAGCUCCUUGGUAAGAGUGGACACGUGCUGUCACUCGGGUGCAGGGUAUGGAGAGCUCCUUGAUAAUAAUGGACACGUGCUGUCACUCGGGUGCAGGGUAUGGAGAGCUCCUUGGUAAGAGUGGACACGUGCUGUCACUCGGGUGCAGGGUAUGGAGAGCUCCUUGGUAAUAGUGGACACGUGCUGUCACUCGGGUGCAGGGUAUGGAGAGCUCCUUGGUAAGAGUGGACACGUGCUGUCACUCGGGUGCAGGGUAUGGAGAGCUGCUUGGUAAUAGUGGACACGUGCUGUCACUCGGGUGCAGGGUAUGGAGAGCUCCUUGGUAAUAGUGGACACGUGCUGUCACUCGGGUGCAGGGUAUGGAGAGCUCCUUGGUAAGAGUGGUCACGUGCUGUCACUCGGGUGCAGGGUAUGGAGAGCUGCUUGGUAAUAGUGGACACGUGCUGUCACUCGGGUGCAGGGUAUGGAGAGCUGCUUGGUAAUAGUGGACACGUGCUGUCACUCGGGUGCAGGGUAUGGAGAGCUCCUUGGUAAGAGUGGACACGUGCUGUCACUCGGGUGCAGGGUAUGGAGAGCUGCUUGGUAAUAGUGGACACGUGCUGUCACUCGGGUGCAGGGUAUGGAGAGCUCCUUGGUAAGAGUGGACACGUGCUGUCACUCGGGUGCAGGGUAUGGAGAGCUCCUUGGUAAUAGUGGACACGUGCUGUCACUCGGGUGCAGGGUAUGGAGAGCUCCUUGGUAAGAGUGGACACGUGCUGUCACUCGGGUGCAGGGUAUGGAGAGCUGCUUGGUAAUAGUGGACACGUGCUGUCACUCGGGUGCAGGGUAUGGAGAGCUCCUUGGUAAGAGUGGACACGUGCUGUCACUCGGGUGCAGGGUAUGGAGAGCUCCUUGGUAAUAGUGGACACGUGCUGUCACUCGGGUGCAGGGUAUGGAGAGCUCCUUGGUAAGAGUGGACACGUGCUGUCACUCGGGUGCAGGGUAUGGAGAGCUCCUUGGUAAUAGUGGACACGUGCUGUCACUCGGGUGCAGGGUAUGGAGAGCUCCUUGGUAAGAGUGGACACGUGCUGUCACUCGGGUGCAGGGUAUGGAGAGCUGCUUGGUAAUAGUGGACACGUGCUGUCACUCGGGUGCAGGGUAUGGAGAGCUCCUUGGUAAGAGUGGACACGUGCUGUCACUCGGGUGCAGGGUAUGGAGAGCUCCUUGGUAAUAGUGGACACGUGCUGUCACUCGGGUGCAGGGUAUGGAGAGCUCCUUGGUAAGAGUGGACACGUGCUGUCACUCGGGUGCAGGGUAUGGAGAGCUGCUUGGUAAUAGUGGACACGUGCUGUCACUCGGGUGCAGGGUAUGGAGAGCUCCUUGGUAAGAGUGGACACGUGCUGUCACUCGGGUGCAGGGUAUGGAGAGCUGCUUGGUAAUAGUGGACACGUGCUGUCACUCGGGUGCAGGGUAUGGAGAGCUCCUUGGUAAGAGUGGACACGUGCUGUCACUCGGGUGCAGGGUAUGGAGAGCUGCUUGGUAAUAGUGGACACGUGCUGUCACUCGGGUGCAGGGUAUGGAGAGCUCCUUGGUAAGAGUGGACACGUGCUGUCACUCGGGUGCAGGGUAUGGAGAGCUCCUUGGUAAUAGUGGACACGUGCUGUCACUCGGGUGCAGGGUAUGGAGAGCUCCUUGGUAAGAGUGGACACGUGCUGUCACUCGGGUGCAGGGUAUGGAGAGCUGCUUGGUAAUAGUGGACACGUGCUGUCACUCGGGUGCAGGGUAUGGAGAGCUCCUUGGUAAGAGUGGACACGUGCUGUCACUCGGGUGCAGGGUAUGGAGAGCUCCUUGGUAAGAGUGGACACGUGCUGUCACUCGGGUGCAGGGUAUGGAGAGCUCCUUGGUAAGAGUGGACACAUGCUGUCACUCGGGUGCAGGGUAUGGAGAGCUGCUUGGUAAUAGUGGACACGUGCUGUCACUCGGGUGCAGGGUAUGGAGAGCUCCUUGGUAAUAGUGGACGCACGCUGUCACUGGGGCGCAGGGUAUGGAGAGCUGGAUGCACAGCUUCAUCAUGACAUGUCAUACUUUCGGAAAGCAAAAGCGGCUUGCGAAGUCCCCUAAGCCCCUUUUAUUCCCCCUAACAGUGGUUUGCUCUCGGUGAUCACCCAGUUCAUACUUAAUGAAAUGAGGAAGAAUGAAGCUCUCCUCUAUGACUGGAUGGAAUUUACAUGUGGUGUUUCCAACACAGCAAAACUUUCGAAACCGAAGCCAGGCUCCAUAUAACACACAGAGAAAGGAUGAUGAAAACCACAUGCUGAAAAAGGAUGUGGAAGUCAGAGGGUGCCAUCUGCAUAGGAAUUCCUGACAUUGAUACUUGUCAUACGAAAAUAACUUCCUUUUUCAUUGGAUCUUCAUAAAAAACAUAUGAAAUGGGCAAGGGACGCAUGAUUAUUCACAUUUCAUAGGGCAGCAGAUAAACAGGAAUUAUGAGUUGCCCAGUUUUACUCCGCUAACAAGGGCUUAUAAAGAGUCCUUUACUUGUACACUUAGAUUUUUCCCUCGAAAUCCAGUUCUUCCUACUAUAGCAUAUCAUCUCAUUAGGUACAAAGAAAAUUCAUUCACAGCCACAGUUUAAUUCCACUUAAAUAAAUUAAUGGUAAUAAAUAAUUUAAUAAAUAAUAAUGCUUCGUAAGAAUUUAUCUGUAAGAUAGGCCUGGGCCCUGUAGCUAAUUUGAUGUGUAUAUUCGGGAGACAAAUGGGACAAUUAGAAAAUACUCAGAAAAUUGCACAGAAAGGAAGGGGUGUUUUGUCCCCGAAAGAAAGGCAAGACGAACGCGAACCUUCAGUCGUUCUCAUGUGGAGUAUUCAUCGUUCAGCGCCAGGAAGUAUCCUGAGCUGAAGGGCGGGUUCUUACAGAGGCCAUCUGAGCUACAGUGGGAAUGUCAGGUUGGACACGAGGCUCACUGUUACUCAUGAAGAUGUUGACACAGAACGACGAUUUCUAUAACCAAAUAUAUAUACUACAUUUGGUGGGGAAGGAAAGGGAACACAAAACCCAGGUCCCAAAGCUCCCUGUUCAGGUCUCUGUGGCACAGCGGCUGUGGCGGAGUUUUGUCUGGAUCCUGUCGUCGUCUAAAGUCAUGGCCUGGACACCUGUAAACACAGGAAGAAUCACCCUUUUCAUACCAAAGUCACAGAGACUUAUGAGCUUUGUGUGAUGGGGUCACCAUGACAUGGGCCUCCACCUGUAUUUUAUUGUUCUCUAGAAUUUUCACCUGUUAUUGGUGUCUUAGUGCCAUGCACAUGCCUUCAUUAUGCCAGAUCUGUGAUUAAUUUCUUUCUGUGUUAAAUUUAUUUCACCUGUUCUGCUGAAUUUGCUGUGAAGCCUUUCUCCCCUAAUACCUUCUCCUCUGCCUCCCUCCCUCCCAUGUAAAUAUUGAUUUAGAUGUCUUUAUAUUAAUGUAAGGUCCUGCCCUUCACAUGGCAUAGAGAAACCCGUGAUGAAUGCCCCCAUUGUCCCUCAGAAAGCAGAGACUUGAGCAGCUGAGAUGCCUCUUCCCAGAGCUGGAAUCCUUCACAGCACUGCCUCUCUGGCAUCCGCUCCUCACACCGCUGGGCCUUUGCCUUUGCCAUUCAUCAUGUCUGCUGUGCUGCCAUAUCUUCCUUUCUAGGCUCUAAAAAAUGGCUUUUGAAAUUCAAAAUGUGAUACAACUACUCAGGCCAAUGUGCCUGCACUAAUAUAUAAGUCAGAUACUAUCUGGUUUUUCUUCUGGAGCUCUAUAAAUAUUUGAUAGAGUCCUUCUAUUUUAGACGGUUGAACCUGGAUCUGGCUACAUGUGUGCAGAAACACAAUGUCAGAAAUCUUUUCUCACCUGGCGGUGGGUGGAUGUGGAAUUCAAUUUGUAACUUUUAGGUCUAACUUUCCUAACUGUGCUUUCUGUCACAAGCCAAAAUCUGCUUUUUGUCUCAAGUUAGCUUUCCGUAAGAAUGAAGGGAGUCCCAUUUUCCAAUCCCCAGAUCUAGACAGAGGUACAGCAGAUUGAAUGAAGAAUAUUCUGGUGUUACUGCUUUAUUGCUAAUGAAUCAAUGAAAGGCAUGGUUUUAAAGCUAUCAAAGUAUAAAUAGAACUUGACAAGGAUAAUAUAAAAUGGACUUAGUAGCUGAAUGAGAAAUGCCGAAACCUCAAAAAGAAUCACAAGAAACAUCAGAAGCCCUGAAGUGUGCGUGCUGUGCACUGCAGGUCAAAUUUAAAUUCUGAGUAACAAGAGGCUUCCUCCUCAGGAGAAGCUGGAAGCAGGAAGGGGAGUCAGCGUACGGCCGGGCCCCUCUUACCUUUGCAGGGUCCCUGCUGUUGAGAUUAGGACCGCAGGUGUGCAGCAGAGAAUCCAGUUGUUUUGCUUUAGAAAGUGCCUGAAGAACAAAUCCUUCGGGCCCCAAAGAUGCUGUCCUGGGAUCUACUUUGCCAUUGCUCCUCAAGUUCAGCCAGUGUUAUGGCAGGUGUCAGCAUCCACCAAAGGGGACCUUCCUGUAAGAUGAAAAAUACUUUUUAAUUUAAAUAUACAUAACACUUCAAAAUGUCCAGUGUCCUUCAAAUUACUUCAAGAAUUUAGAUUUCCCUGUUAUCAAUGAUAAAUAAUCUCCCAAGGCCACUUAGAGAGACUCCCUGAGAAGAAUCGUGUGUUCUAAGUGAGGUUUAACCCUUACAGUCCUUUGAGAAAGAUCGUGUGUACUAAGUGAGGUUUAACCCUUACAGUCCUUUGAGAAGAAUCGUGUGUACUAAGUGAGGUUUAACCCUUAUACUCCUUUGAGGAGGAUCGUGUGUACUAAGUGAGGUUUAACCCUUAGAGUCCUUUGAGGAGGAUCGUGUGUACUAAGUGAGGUUUAACCCUUACAGUCCUUUGAGGAGGAUCGUGGGUACUAAGUGAGGUUUAACCCUUACAGUCCUUUGAGAAGGAUCGUGUGUACUAAGUGAGGUUUUACCCUUACAGUCCUUUGAGGAGGAUCGUGUGUACUAAGUGAGGUUAAACCCUUACAGUACUUUGAGGAUAAUCAUGUAUACUAAGUGAGGUUUAAGCCUUACACUGCUUUGAGAAGGAUCGUGUGUACUAAGGGAGGUUUAACCCUUACAGUCCUUUGAGGAGGAUCGUGUGUACUAAGUGAGGUUUAACCCUUGCAGUCGUUUGAGAAGGAUCGUGAGUACUAAGUGAGGUUUAACCCUUACAGUCCUUUGAGGAGGAUCCUGUGUACUAAGUGAGGUUUAACCCUUAUACUCCUUUGAGAAGAAUCGUGUGUACUAACUGAGGUUUAAUCCUCACAGUACUUGGAGGAGGAUCAUGUAUACUAAGUGAGGUUUAACACUUACAGUUCAUUGAGGAGGAUUUUGUGUACUAAGUGAGGUUUAAACCUCACAGUCCUUUGUGAAGGAUCGUGUGUACUAAGUGAGGUGUAACCCUUACAGUCCUUUCAGAAAGAUCGUGUGUACUAAGUGAGGUGUAACCCUUACAGUCCUUUGAGAAAGAUCGUGUGUACUAAGUGAGGUUUUACCCUUACAGUCCUUUGAGGAGAAUCAUGUGUACUAAGUGAGGGUUAACCCUUACAGUCCUUUGAGGAGAAUCAUGUGUACUAAGUGAGGGUUAACCCUUACAGUCCUUUGAGGAGGAUCGUGUGUACUAAGUGAGGUUUAACCCUUACAGUCCUUUGAGGAGGAUCGUGUGUACUAAGUGAGGUUUAACCCUUGCAGUCGUUUGAGAAGGAUAGUGAGUACUAAGUGAGGUUUAACCCUUAUACUCCUUUGAGAAGAAUCGUGUGUACUAACUGAGGUUUAACCCUCACAGUACUUGGAGGAGGAUCAUGUAUACUAAGUGAGGUUUAAUACUUACAUUUCAUUGAGGAGGAUUUUGUGUACUAAGUGAGGUUAAACCUUGCAGUCCUUUGUGAAGGAUCAUGUGUACUAAGUGAGGUGUAACCCUUACAGUCCUUUGAGAAAGAUGGUGUGUACUAAGUGAGGUUUAACCCUUACAGUCCUUUGAGAAGGAUCGUGUGUACUAAGUGAGGUUUAACCCUUACAGUCCUUUGAGGAGGAUCGUGGGUACUAAGUGAGGUUUAACCCUUACAGUCCUUUGAGAAGGAUCGUGUGUACUGAGGAUUAACCUUUACAGUCCUUUCAGAAGGAUGGUGUGUACUAAGUGAGGUUUAACCCUUACAGUCCUUUGAGAAGGAUCGUGUGUACUAAGUGAGGUUUAACCCUUACAGUCCUUUGAGAAGGAUCGUGUGUAUUAAGUGAGGUUUAACCCUUACAGUGUUUUGAAAAGGAUCGUGUGUACUAAGGUUUAACCACUAUAGUCCUUUUAUGAGAACCAUGUGUACUAAGUGAGGUUUAACCCAUACAGUCCUUUGAGAAGGGUCGUGUGUACUAACUGAGGUUUAACCCUUACAGUCCUUUGACGAGGAUUGUGUGUACUGAGGUUUAACCCUUACAGUCCUUUGAGGAGGAUCGUGUGUACUAAGUGAGGUUUAACCCUUACAGUACUUUGAGGAGGAUCGUGUGUACUAAGUGAGGUUUAACCCUUACAGUCCUUUGAGGAGGAUCAUGUGUACUAAGUGAGGUUUAACCCUUACAGUCCUUUGAGGAGGAUCAUGGGUACUGAGGAUUAACCCUUAUAGUCCUUUGAGAAGAAUGGUGUGUACUAAGUGAAAUUUAACACUUACAGUCCUGUGAGGAGAAUCGUGUGUACUAAGUGAGGUUUAACCCUUACAGUCCUUUGAGAAGGAUCGUGUGUACUAAGUGAGGAUUAACCCUUACAGUCCUUUCAGAGGGAUGGUGUGUACUAAGUGAGGUUUAACCCUUACAGUCCUUUGAGGAGGAUCGUGUUUCCUAAGUGAAGUUUAACCCUUACAGUCCUUUGAGGAGGGUGGUGUGUACUAAGUGAGGUUUAACUCUUACAGUCCUUUGAGGAGGAUCGUGUGUACUAAGUGAGGUUUAACCCUUACAGUCCUUUGAGGAGAAUCAUGUGUACUAAGUGAGGGUUAACCCUUACAGUCCUUUGAGGAGGAUCGUGUGUACUAAGUGAGGUUUAACCCUUACGGUCCUUUGAGGAGGAUCGUGUGUAACUAAGUGAGGUUUAACCCUUACGGUCCUUUGAGGAGGAUCUUGUGUACUAAGUGAGGUUUAACCCUUACAGUCCUUUGAGGAGGAUCGUGUGUACUAAGUGAGGUUUAAACCUUACAGUCCUUUGAGAAGGAUCGUGUGUACUAACUGAGGUUCAACACUUACAGUCCUUUGAGGAGGAUCCUGUGUGCUAAGUGAGGUUUAAACCUUACACUCCUUUGAGGAGAAUCAUGUGUACUAAGUGAGGUUUAACCCUUACAGUCCUUUAAGGAGGAUCUUUUGAACUAAGUGAGGUUUAACCCUUACAGUCCUUUGAGGAGAAUCAUGUGUACUAAGUGAGGUUUCACCCUUACAGUCCUUUGAGAAGGAUCUUCUCUACUAAGUGAGGUUUAACCCUUAGAGUCCUUUGAGGAGGAUCGUGUGUAGUAAGUGAGGUUUAACCCUUACAGUCCUUUGAGAAGGAUCUUCUGUACUAAGUGAGGUUUAACCCUUACAGUCCUUUGAGAAGGAUCGUGUGUACUCAUGUUUAACCCCUAUAGUCCUUUGAGGAGAAUUGUGUGUACUAAGUGAAGUUUAACCCUUAUACUCCUUUGAGAAGGAUCGUGUGUACUAAGGGAAGUUUAACCCUUAUAGUCCUUUGAGGAGGAUUGUGUGUACUAAGUAAGGUUUAACCCUUAUAGUCCUUUGAGAAAAAUGGUGUGUACUAAGUGUGGUUUAACCCUUACAGUCCUUUGAGGAGGGUCUUGUGUACUACGUGAGGUUUAACCCUUACAGUCCUUUGAGAAGGAUCGUGUGUAUUAAGUGAGGUUUAAUCCUUACAGUCCUUUGAGGAGGAUCGUGUGUACUAAGUGAGGUUUAACGCUUACAGUCCUUUGAGAAGGAUCGUGUGUACUAAGUGGGGUUUAACCCUUACAGUCCUUUGAGGAGGAUCUUGUGUACUAAAUCAGGUUUAACCCUUACAGUCGUUUGAGGAGGAUCGUGUGUGCCAAGUGAGGUUUAACCCUUACAGUCCUUUGAGAAGGAUCGUGUGUACUAAUGUUUAACCCCUAUAGUUCUUUGAGGAGAAUUUCGUGUACUGAGGUUUAACCCUUACAGUCCUUUGAGGAGGAUCGUGUGUACUAAGUGAGUUUUAACCCUUACAGUCCUUGGAGGAGGAUCAUGUGUAGUAAGUGAGGUUUAACCCUUACAGUCCUUUGAGAAGGAUUGUGUGUACUAAGGUUUAACCCCUAUAGUCCUUUUAGGAGAAUUGUGUUUACUAAGUGAGGUUUUACCCUUACAGUCCUUUGAGGAGGAUCGUGUGUACUAAGUGAGGUUUAACCCUUACAGUCCUUUGAGGAGGAUCAUGUGUACUAAGUGAGGUUUAAUCCUUACAGUCCUUUGAGAAGAAUCUUGUGUACUAAGUGAGGUUUGUCCCUUACUGUCCUUUGAGAAGAAUCGUAUGUACUAAGUGAGGUUUAACCCUUACAGUCCUUUGAGGAGGAUCGUGUGUACUAAGUGAGGUUUAACAUUUACAGUCCUUUGAGAAGGAUCGUGUGUACUAAGUGAUGUUUAAGCCUCAGAGUCCUUUGAGAAGGAUCGUGUGUACUAAGUGAUGUUUAACCCUUACAGUCCUUUGAGGAGGAUAAGAAGAGUCUCCCUUGUGCAGGGACAGUCACUGAAGUUUGGGGAAGUCUAGGAAUUUUAAAAGAACAGGAUUUUGGAAAUGAAUUCAGGUCAAUGUUCAAGCCCCAUUCUGCCCUUUUGAGUGGCCCCGAGAUGGCCCAGGGCCUGCCCUCCAGGACCUUGGCGGAGGUGGGGGCCAACGGGUUCCUCUUCUAACAGACUGUGGUGGAAACAGUAUCAGUUUCCUUAUGACCAACACACUAGUGAGGGAAUAUCAUGAUAAAUUUAUGACUGAAACACCUUACGUUUGUGCAGUUCACGUACACAAUGGGGAUGUAAUCGUAGGUGGUUGGAUGUGGCGUCUUCAGAGCUUAGGGUGCUUGUGAGUUAAGGGAGCUUGGUGGUCACGGGUUUUAGGGCUUUCUUUCUGAGAAGCAGAGCUAUCGAUUGCUACCUAAUUGAAAAGAUUGUGUGAGUCUGUAAUGUUUUUCUCUUAUUCACUAGAACACUUUAUCAGCCUGACAACAUUGGAAAGGAAACAGAAGCUGCCAGGGAAGCAGGUGUGAAAACAGCUCCAGUUACUCAGGCAAGGCUGUGGCUGCUCACCCGUGGCCCUGGCUCACGCAAAACUCUCCAGAAUUAGGGGUGCUCUUGCAUGGGGGUGCUCUGGUGUGUGGGUGCUCUGGUGUGUGGGUGCUUCGGUGUAUGGGUGCCCUGGUGUGUGUGUGGUCUGGUGUGUGGGUGCUCCAGUGUAUGAGUGCCCUGGUGUGUGGGUGCUCUGGUAUGUGGGUGCCCUGGUGUACGGGUGCCCCGGUGUUCGGGUGCCCUGGUGUGUGGGUGCUCUGGUGUGUGGGUGCUCCAGUGUAUGAGUGCCCUGGUGUGUGGGUGCUCUGGCAUGGGGGUGCUCUGGUGUGUGGGUGCUCUGGUGUAUGGGUGCCCUGGUGUGUGCGUGCCCUGGUGUAUGGGUGCCGUGGUGUGUCAGUGCCCUGGUGUGUGGGUGCUCUGGUGUGUGGGUGCCCUGGUUUACGGGUUUCCUGGUCUGUGGGUGCCCUGGUGUAUGGGUGCCCUGGUGUGUGGGUGCUCUGGUGUACGGGUGCCCUGGUGUACGGGUGCCCUAGUGUGUGGGUGCUCUGGUGUGUGGGUGCCCUGGCGUGUGGGUGCCCUGGCGUGUGGGUGCCUGGCGUGUGGGUGCUCUGGCAUGUGGGUGCUCUGGUGUACGAGUGCCCUGGUGUGUGGGUGCUCUGGUGUGUGAGUGCCCUGGUGUGUGGGUGCUCUGGUGUGUGGGUGCCCCAAUAUGUGGGUGCCCCGGUGUACAGGUGCCCCGGUGUACGGGUGCUCUUGUGUGUAGGUGCUCUGGUGCGUGGGUGCUUUGCUGUAUGGAUGCUGUGAUGUGCAGGUUUAUUUUCCAAAAGUUAGGUAAGAACAUCACUCAAGAUGAUUGAGUCUUUUUCUAAUUCCAAAGGCACUUUAAGGUUUCAGAGAGCCUUGGAUUGUUUAAUAGAGAAGACAUGGCAGAACAUAAACCAUAGAAGGUGUCUGAGAUGACUGUAAUUUUAAACAAGUUCCUAAUAUUAAUACACUGCAAAAUAUCAUUUAAUUUUAAUAGAAACAACUUUUACUAUUAUCUUUCCUUUUUUUCUUUCUCGUUGAAAUGAAGACUUAACAUCAAAUUCAGCAAAACAGAUGAAAUCAAUUAAAAUAUAACAUGGCGUGCAGGGCAGGCACGGCCUCCUGCCCCUGGGGAGCUGGAGCCCUCACGGAGUCCUGUGUGUGGCUGUGCUUUCUGGGGCUGAGCAGAUGAGGUAGCUCAGUUCCCCAGGAAUCAGAACCGAGGCGGAGCUGUGCCACCCCAGCCUCCAGGGUGAACAGCAACAGCUCCCUGAAACUGGACGAGCUCCCCAGAGUUCAAGCUACAGAGGUUCCUGCCUCCCCAGGGCAUGGAGUCCUCACUGCACUGCUCCCCACCUUGUGGGCCCCAGGCUGCGCUGGCAUCUUGCCAUUCCCGGGUCUUUGCUGCUGCUGCACUGGCCUCACAGGGCCUGGGCCACUGCCAUGUCCUGCCAUCCCUGAGUCACUAGUGUGUGGCACCUCAUCUCCUGGGCUCUAGUUGCUGCUGUGCCCUGUUGGUUUUGGGUCCAGGAUUGCAGCUGUGCCCUGUAUCCCAAGAGCUGAGCUUCUGAAGAACCCCUUAUCUCCCAGGGCCAUGACAGUGCUAUGUCCAGCCCCCCAGGGUCAGAACCAGAGCUAAAACCUGGCCCCCCAGGUCUGAACUGCCAGAGUCUGCCUCAGAACAACAGACCCCAGCUUUGUGGACAAUCUGAAGCCACCUGAGCCCCAGAGAGUGAAUCUGCACCUUGAGCACCGGAUGCCACAAGGGCUUCACGUCACCCCAGGGCCCUGGUUCCACAGCUGCCCUGUGCACCUGUGCCCUGGAUCUCAGUGCCACUGCAGCUGCUUGUGGGCCGUGUCAGACCCUGCGCUGAGAAAGAUCCCCUCAGCUGAGACUCCCCUCUACAGAGAAGUCAAAAGUAGUAGGAUACAUGAAGCCCUUGCCACCAAGGACCCUAGACUUAUGCUGCCACCAUCAUUGUCCUGAAUUCCUGCAGCCUAUGCCACUUAGACACCCACAGUCAUUCCUGACAUUCAUUACAACUGAAGAACCUGCACAGAGACUAUACCCCUGCACCCUGUCCAACCAGCACCCUCAGGCCCAUCUGUAUGUGAAAAUCUUCCCCUACAAAAGGCACUACUUAAAAAUUAGAAGAGAUAAGAAUCAGAUAGCAUAAAAAGGAACCAGACAGAAAUCUCAAAGCUGAAUAACUCAAUGAAAUCAUAAAAAAAUUCAGUAGAGGACUUCAAUAGCAGACCUAGAUUAAGCAGCAGAAAAAAAAAAUCUGUGAACUUGAAGAGAGGUCUUUUGGAAUGACUCAUUUGGGGAGGUGAAUAGAAAACGGAAUAAAAAUAGUGAAGAAAGCCUGUGGCACUCACAGGAAGCAAUCAGAUGAAGAAAGUUCUGUAUUAUGGGACUGAGAAGGAGCAAAAACAGAAAAAAAGGACAGAAAGGUUAUUUAAUAAAAUAAUUACUGAAAACUUGGAAGUUUUCAGUCUUGGGAGAGAUAUGGGCAUUCAAUUUCAUGAAGCUCAAAGAUCACCAAACAUAUUCAACCCAAAGAGGUCUUCAUCAAGGAUCGUUUUAAUCAAAGUGUCAAAAGUCAAAGGCAAAAAAAGGAUAAUUUUAAAUGAAGCAAAAGUGUCAAGUUGCAUAUAAAGGAAUCUCCAUUAGUCUAUCAGUGGAUUUCUCAGCAGAAAACUUGAAAGCCAGGAAAGAAUAGUAUGAUACCUACAGGGAAAACAAACAAACACAAAAACCAUUAGCUAAGAAUUCUGUGCUCAGCAAAGCUGCCCUUCAGAAAUGGAGAAAGUAAGUCUUUCCUAGAUAAAAAAAAGAAAAAAGCUGAUGGAUUUCAUAAUCACUAUGCUUGCUGUAUCUGAAAUGCUUAAAGGAGUACUUCAAGCAGCUAGAAAAGUGUAAUCACUAUCACAAAUACACUUGAAGGUACCAAACUCACGGGUAGAAGGAAGUACGUAGUCAAAUUCAGCAUAGUCCAGUGUCAUCAUGGUGGUGUGUAACCCAUACAUGUCUCCAGUAUGAAGGUAAAAAGUCAAAACAGUAAAACUAAGGCCAUAAUAACUUUUUAAGGUAUACACAAUGUCAAAAGAUGCAAAUCGUGACAUCAAGAACAUAAACUGUGGAGGAGAAGUUAAAGGCUCGUUUUUUUUUUUUUUGUAUAAAAAAAUGUAAGUUGUCUGCAGCUUAAAAUAGUAGACUAUAAGAUAUUUUACAUAAGCUUCAUAAUAUCCACAAAACAACAACAGCAACAAAAUGAUAGCAGACAUACAAAGGGUGAAAAUAAAGGAAUCAAAGCUGAGCACCACAGAAAAUUAUCACGUUACAAAGGCAGACGAGAGUGGAGGAAAGGGACAGAGGAUCUGCAAACAACAAAAAAAAUAAGAGAAUGGCAUUGCUCAUUUCUUAUCUGUCAAUAAUCACCUUGAAUAUUACAAAUAAGAAAAUAAGAGAAUGACUGGUCAUUCCUUUUCUAUCAAUAAUCACUUUGAAUAUUACAAAUAAGAAAAUAAGAAAAUGUCAUUGGUCAUUCUUUAUCUAUCAAUGAUCACCUUGAAUAUUACAAACAACAAGAAAAUGAGAAAAUGGCAUUGAUAAUUCCUUCUCUAUCAAUAAACACCUUGACUAUUACAACAAGAAAAUAAGAAAAUGGCAUUGAUCGUUCCUUAUCUACCAAUAAUCACCUUGAAUAUUACAACAAGAAAAUGAGAAAAUGGUAUUGAUCAUUCUUUCUCUAUCAGUAAUUACCUUGGAUAUUCCAAACAAGAAAAUAAGAAAAUGGCAUUUGUCAUUCUUUAUCAAUAAUCGCCUUGAAUAUUACAAAACAACAAGAGAAGAAAAUGGUAUUGGUUAUUACUUAUCUAUCAAUAAUUACUUUGAAUAUUACAAACAAGAAAAUAAGAGAAUUGCAUUGGUCAUUCCUUAUCUAUCAAUCACCUUGAAUAUUACCAACAACAAGAAAAUGAGAGAAUUACAUUGGUCAUUCCUUAUCUAUCAAUAAUCACCUGGAAUAUAAAUUGAUUACAUUCUCCCAUCAAAAGACAUAUAGUGGUGAAGUAGACUGAAAAAGAGAUGAUCCCAACUAUAUACUGGCUAUAAGAGACCCGCUUUAUCUUUAAGGACACACACAUAUUAAAAGUGAAGAUAGGGAAACAAUAUUCCAUGCAAAUGGUAGCCAAAAGAGAGAAGGGGUAGUUAAACUUAACAUCUGAUAAAACAGACUUUAAAUCAAACUGGUCACAAGAGACAAAGAAGGCCUUUAUCUAGUGAAAAGGGGAUAAUUUAUCAGGAGGACAUAACAAUCAUAAACAUAUAUGCAUCCGACAUUGGAGUACUUAAAUACAUAAAGCAAAUAUUAAUGAACAUAAAGAGAUAAAUACAUAGCAAUACAACAGUAAUAGGGGACUUCAGCACCCCACUUUCAACAAUAGAUAGUUCAACUAGACAGAAAAUCAAUAAGAAAAUACAGGACUUGAAUUGCACUUUGGGCCAAAAAGACUUAUCAGAUAUAUAAAGAACUUUCCAUGCAAUAGCAGCAAAAUACACAUUUUUCUAUAGCACACAUGGAACACACACAUGGAUAGACCAUAUAUUAGGCCAUAAAACAAGUCUUAACAAAUUUUGUAUUGCAAUUCUAUCUAGUAUCAUCUCUGACCACAUGGAAGGAAACUAAAAAUCAGUAACAGGAGGAAUCUUGGAAAAUUCAUAAAUAGGUAGAAAUUAAACAGUAUUGCCCUGAACAAUCAAUGGGUCACAGAAGGAAUCAAAAGUGAAAUUUGAAAACUAUCUAUCUUGAGACAAACAACAACAGAAAUACAACCUACCAGAACUUCUGGGAUGCCGCAAAAACAGUUGUGAGAAGGAAAUUGAUAGUGAUAAAUACCUACAUUAAAACAAAGAUCCUAAAUAGCCUAACAUUAAGCCUCAAGAAAUGAGAUAAAGAACAACAAAGUAAACCAAAAGUUUACAGAAGGAAGGAAAGAGGAUGAGAACAGAAAUAAGUCAAACAGACAAUAGUAAACAAUAAAAAGAAUUAGUAAAACUAAGAAUUGUUUUUAAAAAAAAAUAAAAUUGGCAAACUCUUCAUCUGUAUUAGUCCGUUCUCACGCUGCUAUAAAGAACUGUCUGAGACUGGGUAAUUUAUAUGAAGGAAAGUGUUUGACUCACAGUUCCGCAUGGCUGGGGAGGCGUCAGAAGACUUACAAUCAUAGUAGAAGGUAAAGGGGAAGCAAGGCACCUUCUUCAUAAGGUGGCAGGAAAGAGAAUGAAGGCAGGAGGAACUAGCUACCACUUGUAGAACCAUCAGACCUUGUGAGAACCCACUCAGUAUCAUGAGAACAGCAUGGGGGAAACUGCCCCCAUGAUCCAAUCACCUCCACUUGUUCUCUCCCUUGACACGUGGGGAUCAGGGUGAUUGCAGGGAUUAUAAUUGAAGAUGAGAUUUGGGUGGGAACACAAAGCCUAACCAUAUUAUAAUCUAAGAAACAGAAGUUUCAAAUAAAUAAAAAAAGUGAAGGCAUUACCAUGGACACCUCAGAAAUGAAAGGAUCAUAAGGGACUAUUAUGAACUAUUAUAUGCCAGAAAAUUGGACUACCUAGAGGAAAUGGUUAAAUUUGUGGAAAAAUACAACCUGCCAAGUUUGAGUCAGGAAAAAAUAGAAAGACUGAACUGACCAAAACCAAAUAGGGACAUAGAAAAAGUAAUCAAAUCCUUUCAACAAAAGAAAGCAUGGGACCAGAUGGCUUCAUGGCUGAAUUAUACCAAAUAUUCAAAGAAGAAAUAAUAUGAAUACUUCUCAAACUCUUUCAACAAAUAAAUCUAGAGGGAAUAAUUAUGUAUACAUUUUUAAAAGCCAGCAUCACCGUGACACCUAAGCUGAACAAAGAUGUCACUAACAAUGAAAACUACAGGCCAAUUUUUCUGAUGAACAAAUGACAGAAACAUUCUCAUAAUGACUUUAGCAAGCCAAGUCCAACAGCACAUUAGAAAGAUUACAUGUCAUGACCAAGUAGGAUUCAUCCAUGGCAUGUGAGGCCAGUUUAACAUUUUCAGAUUAACCAAUGUGACACAUCACAUUAACAGACUGAUGCAGAAAAAUCAUUUGACAAAGCCCAAUAUCUAUGAUAAAAAAUCUCACCAGUUCAGGUAUAGACAGCAUGUUCACAAUAAAGCUAUUUAUGAAAAAUUCCUAGCUAGCAUUAUAAUCAAUAUGAACAAACGCUUUAACAUUAAGAUCCUCUGCAAGACAAGGAUGCCCAGUCUUGCCGAUUUUAUUCAACAUGACACUGGAAGUACUUGCAAUUAGCAAUCAGACAAAAAAAAAAAAAAAAAAAAGGCAUCCGAAUAAGAAAGGAAGAAGUAAAGUUAUCUAUUUGCAGAUGGCAUGAUUCUAUUUGUAAAAACCCCAAAGAUUCCACAGAAAAACUGUUAGAACCAAUAAUUCAGUAAAGUUUCAGGAUAUGAAAUUCAUAUGCAAAAAUUAAUAGCAUUGUCAUACACAAAUAAUAGCUGAAAAAGAAAUCAAAACAAUCCCAUUUAUUAAUGCAAGCAUCAGAAAAAAAUAAAAUAUUUAGCAAUAAGUAUAACCAAGGAGAUAAAAGACCUAUACAAUGAAAACUGUAAAAUAUUGAUGAAGACAAUUCAAAACAUUGAAGAAGAUACCAAUAAAUGGAAAGAUAUUUUGGGCUCAUGUCUGGGCUCAUCAUAAUUAAUAUUGCUAAAAUAUCUAUGAGCCAAAGUUAUAUAUAGAUUCAGUGUAAUCCUUAUCAAAAUCCCAAUGACAUUUUUCACAGAAACAGAAAAAACAAUUCAAAUAUUCAUAUGGAAUCACAAAAGACCCUGAAUGGCCAAACAGUUCUAAGAAAAAAAAAGUUGGAGGCAUCACACUUUCUGAUUUAGAUUAUAUUACUAUAGUAAUCAAAACAGUAUGGUGUUGGUAUAAAAAACAGACACCUACACCAGUGGAGCAGAAUAGAAAGCCCAGAAGUAAAACUAAACGUACAUGCUCAACUAAUUUUGGACUAAGGGCAUCAGGAGGAUACAAUGGAGAAUGUAUAGUCUUUUCAAUAAAUGUUGCUGGGAAAACUGGACUUCCACAUGUGAAAGAGUGAAAUUGGACUCUUGUCUUACACCGUAUAGGAAACCUACCAAAAAUGGAUGAAAGUCUUAACUGUAAGAUCAGAAGCCAUAAAACUCCUAGAAGAGAACGUUGGAGAAGAGCUCGUUGAUAUUGGCCUUGGCAAUAAUUUCUUGGCUGUCACACCACAACCUCAGACUACAAAAGCACAAAUAGAUAAAUUGGACUACAUCAAACUGAAGUUCCUGCACAGCAAACAAGACCAGCAGCCUAUGGAUUGGGAAAGUAUAUUUGCAAAACAUGUAUCUGAUAAGAGGUUAAUAUUCAAAAUUUAUGAAGAAUUCAUUCAGGUUAAUAGAACAAGUAAACCAAUUAAAAAUGGGCAAGGCAGAUACAGAAAGACAAGCGCCACAUGCUCUCACUUAUAUGUGGAAUCUAAAACAAUUGAACUCAUGGAAGCAGAGAGUAGAAUGAUGGUCACAGAAGCUGGGGAUUGGAGAAUGGGGAGAUGACGGUCAGAGGGCACAGACUCUCAGUUGUGCAGGAAGAAUUUUUUUUAAGUUCUAUUGCACAGUGUGGCAAAGAUAGCUUUUUAAUAGAUUAUUGUACAUUUCAGAAUUGCUAAGAAAAUUAUCUUGUUUUCAUUAUAAAAACAUGUGAAGUAUUUGAGGUCAUAGAUAUGUUAACCAGCUUGCUUUCAUUAUCCCAUAUUGCAUUCAUAAAUCAUAACAUUAUUUUUACCCUGUAAGUUUAUAUGAUUAUAAAUUGUCAAUUACAAUUUGAAAAUAUAUAGGGUGGAAUAUUACUCAGUCUUUUUUUAAUUUUUCUCAGACAGAGGCUUGCUUUGUUGCCCAGGCUGGAGUGCAGUGGUGCGAUCUCAGCUCACUACAAGCUCUGCUUCCCAGGUUCAUGCCAUUCUCCUGCCUCAGCCUCCUGAGUAGCUGGGACUACAGGUGCUCGCCACCACGCCCGGCUAAUUUUUUUUGUAUUUUUAGUAGAGACGGGGUUUCAUUGUGUUAACCAGGAUGGUCUCGAUCUCUUGACCUCAUGAUCCUCCCACCUUAGCCUCCCAAAAUGCUGGGAUUACAGGCGUGAGCCACCGCGCCCGGCCUACUCAGUCUUAAAGAAGGAGGAGGUCCUGCCCUUUGUCACAACAGGGUUGAACCUGGAGGACGCUAUGCCAGGGGAAACAAGCCAGACAUUAAAGGGAAAUACCACAUGACCUCACUUAUGGGUGGAACCUGACGAAAAGGUCAAACACGCAGAGAAGGAGAAUAAUACAGUGGUCACCAGAAGUGAGGAGAUGGUGGUGGGGAGGAAUGAGGAGCUGGAGGUCAGAGGAUGCAAAGCCGUGCACAAGUAGGCGAGCGAGUUGAGAGGUCCAGUGCUCAGCAUGAGGACUGAAGGUCACACAAUCAUACCGUGUUGGGGAUUCCUGCUACAUUUUAGCUGCUCUUGACACACACAAAACAAAACAAAACAAAAAUAUGGGUAAUCAGGUGAGAUGAUGGAUAUGUUAAUUUGCUUCACUAUAGUAACCAUUUUACUAUCUAUAACAUCUUUUUGUAUGCCUUAGACAUACUGUUAUUAUUAAUAGUAACAAAAAUCUACUGGACACCCACAGGACAUUCACAAUUUGAAUCAACACCAGCAUUAACCUUCAAAUUAUGUUAAAUAAAACUUUUUAUUUAAAAGUCUUCAUUUUAAUACGCUAAAUAUUCAGUUACUAUAAAUAGCUACUAAAGUCUGGCUGCUCGAGAGAUUUCUUGCAUAGCAUAUUUAUUUCAUAAUAUUAAAACUUCAUUUCUUCAUUUAUGAACUUUAUUAUCAAAGUAGAGAUUUUUUGUCCUUUUUUAAAUCAAGAGUGUGUAACAGGAAGCUGAGUUUUCCUCUCCUCUGUCCCUUCCUCCUGUCCUCCUCUUGCUUCUUCCCUCUCCCUCCCUUCCUUUGCCUUCAAAGCACCCAUGCAUUUGUGCAUAUUUUUAUUUGUAUCCUUAGGUUUGAAGUUUGCUGCUUUCUUCUAAUAUCUUGGUGUUAGUCAUUCAAAACCCUUAAUAACUACCAUACCUCCAAAACAGAAUUGUUUUCUAAGAUGAGUUAUUGUAAAUAUAAAUCACAGAAGGAAAGCAUACUUUAGAUGGACAUGCUACUUUUCUUAAAGAUUUACAAUUAAAGAUUUACAGUAAAUACAUGUCAGCUGUUUUAAUUUUGAUGUGUGUUUUGCUUAAUUUAUUCUCAAUUGAGAAACUUUUUCUCUCUUGGGGCAAAAAGUAACACAUUAGAUCAGUUAGUAAAUUUCAGAACAGGAUAUGAUGAUAGAAUGAAUGACAGAAGUAGACAGUAGGGUGUGGUGUACAGGGAUAGGGUGAAGCUGUGUUUUUUUUAAUUAACACAUAAUUGUACAUAUUUAUGGGGUACAUAAUGAUGCUUCAAUACAUACAAUUUAUAGUGCUCAGAUCAGGAUAAUUAUCAUAUUCAUCAUCUCCAACAUUUAUUAUUUCUUUGUGUUGGGAAUAUUCAAUAUGCUCUCUUCUAGCCAUUUGAAAAUAAACAAUAUAUUAUUGCUAACUAUCAUUAUUCUACAGUGCUAUAGAACACUAGAAGUAUUCCUCCUAUCUAGCUGUAACUGUGUAUCCUUAAAAAAAUCUCUCCACAUCUCUCUUACCUCCUCCCCUUCCCAACAUCUAGUAACCUCUAUUCUACUCCUUAGUUCUAUGAGACCAGCUUCCGCAUAUGAGUGAGAACAUGCAGUGUUUAACUUCCUGGGCCUGGCUGACUUCACUUAAAGUAAUGUCCUACAGGUUCACCCACUCUGCCACGAAUGGGAGUGUUUCAUUCUGUGUGUGGCUGAAUAGUGCUCCACUGUGUAUAUACACCACGUUGUCUUUAUUCAUUCACCUGUUGUGGGACACUUAGCUUUGUUCCGUAUCUUGGCUAUUGCAAAUAUUGCUACAAUUAACAUGGGGUGCAGAUAUAUCUUUGACAUACUGAUUUUCUUCCCUUUGGAUAAAAGUGGCAGGUUUGCCAGAAUCAUAUGGUAGUUCUAUUUUUAGUUUUUUUGAGAAAGCCCAUAUUUUUCAUGUUGGCUAUACCAGUUUACAUUACCACCAGCAGUGUGAGUUUCCCUUCCUCUGCACCCUCACCAACAUUUGUCAUUUUUUGGUCUAUUUAGUAAUAACCAUUCUAACCGGGAUAAGAUAAUAUCUUAUUGUGGUUUUUAUUUGCAUUGCCCUGAUGAUUAGUGAUUUUAAGCAUUUUUUCAUAUAUUUAGUCAUUUUUCUUCUUUUGAGAAAUGUCUAUUCAGCUGAUAUGCAUACUUUUCAGUAGGAUUAUUUGUUUUUUGCUGUCGAGAGAUUUGAGUUCCUUGUAUAUGCUGAUAUUAAUCCUUUGUCAAAUGAAUAGUUUGAAAAUAUUUUCUCCCAUUCCGUGGCUUGUCUCUUCACUCUGUUGUUUCCUUUGCUGUGCAGAACCUUUUUAGUUUGAUAUAUCCCAUUUGUUUAUUUUUGCUUUUGUUAUCUGUGUUUUUGAGGUUUUAUACAAUUUUUUCUCAGACCAGUGUCCAGAACCAUUGCCUCUAUUUUUAUCAUCUAGUCGUUUUAUAGUUUUGGGUCUUACAUUUAGAUCUUUGAUCUAUUUUGAGUUGAUUUUUUUAUACAAAGUGAGAGAUGGGAGUCCAGUUUCCUUCUUCUGCAAGUGAAUAGCCAGUUCUCCCAGCACCAUUUAUUGAAGAGAAAAUGUUCUCAAUGUAUGUUCUUGGUGCCUUUGUAAAAAAAAAAAUCAGUUGUCUGUAGAUACAUGGAUUAAUAUCUGGGAUACUUAUCUUGUUUGAUUGCUGUAUCUAUUUUUUGCCUGUACCACGUUGCUUUGGUUACUAUAGCUUUAUAAUAUAAUCUUAGGAAGUGUAAUACCUCCAACUUUAUUCUUGUUUCUCAGGAUUGCUUUGGCUACUUGGGGCUUCAUGUAGUUCUGCGCAAAUUUUACAAUUUUCUUUUUUAUUUCUGUGAAGAAUGUCAUUGGUAUUUUGAUAGGGUUUGCAUUUAAUUUUUAGAUCGCUUUGGGGAGUAUGUUCAUAUUAACAGUCUUGAUUUUUCCAGUCUGUGAACACGUUAUGUCAUUCCUUUGUGUCAUCAUCAAUUUUUUCUAUCAGUGUUUCAUAGUUUUCCUUGUAGGGAUCUUCCAUAUCCUUGGUUAAAUUUAUUCCAAGGGGUGUGUGUGUAUGUGUGUAUGUGUGUGGCUAUUGUAAAUGGGAUUGGUUUACUGAUUUUUUUCAGCAAGUUCAUUGUUCGUACUUAGAACACUAUUGAUUUCUGUACGUUGAUUUUGUAUUCUGUAACUUUACUGAAUUCAUUUAUCAGUGCUAAGAGUUUUUUGGUAGAACCUUUAGGUUUUUCUAUACAAGAUCAUGUCAUCUGCAAAAAGGGACAAUUUGACUUCCUCUUUUUCAACUUGGAUGUCCUUUAUUUAUUUCUCUUGCCUGAGUGCUCUAGCUAGGACUUCCAGUACUAUGUUGAGUAAGAGUGGUGAGAGUGGGCAUCCUUGUUUUGUUCCAGAUUUCAGCUUUUCCAUUAAGCAUAAUGUUAGCUGUGGGUUUGUCAUAUGUGGCCUUUAUUGUUUUGAAGUACUUUUCUUCUGUACCUAUUUACUGAGAGUUUUUGUCAUGAAGAAGUGUUAAAUUUUAUUAAAUGCUUUUUUUUUCUGAAUCUAUUUAGAUGAUCAUAUGGUUUUUAAUUUGCCAUUCUAUAAGGAAUGCAAUUUAUUCAUUUUCGCAUACUGUGAAUAAUGGAAUCAAGAUUAUAUCUCGAGUCUAUUCAUUUCACCAUUUGGGGCUGUAUAAAGACAAAAUUGCUUUUUAAAAAUGAGCAAAAUAAUUAUAUACAUUUUAUUAUACAUAUGAAUACAUAAAAAAAUUUGAAAAAUGUAUUCCAUGGAUUUGAAUUUACCUUUGUGUUAUUAUGGAAGUUUUCUUCUUUCAACAGGCUUUGCAACAUAAUGAAUAUCUGCCUUACACAUUUAUUCAUAACUUUCAUUAUUUCUCUUUCGUUUAAGUGAUGCCUCCAUCAACACAAAAUGCACAGUACAGAAAUAGUAAGUGUUUGAUAAAUGAAUACAAGCUCUGGUCUCCCUGCUUCUCUCAGACCGUCACAGUUUAAUCUGAGUUUCCUGUGCCAACUUUCAAUAUUGUUUAUAUACUGCCAUGAUAUGGUGGAGGGUGAAAACUGUGUUAGAAACUAGGACUUCUGCUUGGUGUUUUCUUGUGGACAGGUUCUGCACUGGACUAACAGACACUGGAAAUCUUCUCGUCCAGGGCUGAUAGCCAUCAGCCAGGAUGAGAGUGCACAGGGAAUGCUCAGUUUGUCUUUUCACAGCCACUUAAUGUGACUUUCUGUUAUUCCAGUUGAUUUUUUAAAAAUGAAAUCUGCAUUUUUGACUUGGAAACUGUUGGGAAACAAUUCAGUUUAUGAUUAGGAAAUGAUUACUCAUCUACUUCCAGUGCUGAAGGGGAGAUCAUACACCUAGGAAUAAGUGUCUAGCCUUUCCAUCUUCAGAGAAAAAUGUUAUACAGCAGAGGAAUCGACCUCGAAUAAACGACAUAUACAUUUUAUGCAGGCCAUUUUCAGAAAGUACCAAAAGUGAGAUGAGACAGUUGGUUCUUGAGAUAAGCUAAAGGAUUUGCUAUUCGUUCAUUCAUUUUUCUAAGUCUUCUAACAAAUGAUUUCCUAAGAAAACUACAGGUGGUUCUCACUAUUUAGCUCCUCUGCAGAACAUCCUUCUUUGACGCUGUUUUAGAAAGUCACUGGCCUUUACCAGAAGUCUUUAUGAUAAAUGACAAGAUGAAGUUUGUAUCUGCAUGUCCUGCAAACAUGCUUUUGAACUCAGUGUCCAUUAUGGUACAUCGUUUCUUUUAUAUAAAGGUCUAUAUCAUUAUUUGAGAAUUCCUUCCCAGGGAAAUGUGUCUCUUCUGGUAAAUAGACACAAAUAUACAAUUUUGGAUAAAUUUGGAAAUUAAUAAUUUCAUCACGGUUGUCUCAUCUGAGACAAACCAUAGAGCCAAACCAUAAAGUCAAAUAAGAAGGUCAAGUUUGUGACCGCAUUAAUUUAACUUUGUAUGUAUUAUUUGUCAUUCUAAGUAGUCCUUAAUGUUCCAUGUUUUAAAUUUAGCAAUUGUAAUAUGCAUAUAACUUACGGCAUUUCACCUUUAAUCCUUUUGAAGUGAAACUGGAAACCUCAACCACUUCUGGUUGUCAUGGUGUUGAGUAGGGCUUGGAGGAUUUCUGAUGAGCUGUGCAAUAGACUCUGCCAUCAAUAAUACAUCAUUGCAAAGUUUAUUGAGCCUGGACAAUGUGGCUUCUUAUCAUCAAGAGAAUGCCUUUAAAUACCUCUUUAAUAUUUUAUAACAUGUCAUCUUCAUGGAAUUUAAUAUAUAAAAUAUUUGAAGGUGGUGUUCACAAGUUGUAAUAAAAAUUCUUGCAGGCCAUACAUGCACUUAACAUUUGUAGGGAGCAAGUCUACUUCUUAUUGUAGAGUUCCUGACAAUAAGAGUUACAGGCAAAAGAACUCAUUCAUCUUACAUUCUUGGCCAAAAAACUUAAAAGCCAUAUGUGCCUGUCUUAUUUUUCUUGCUUGUUUUACACAAUAUGAGCAAUGAAAGUAUUUCUGAGUCUGUGAGUCUCUGGCUUCCUUUACUGCUUCUCCUGAGUAAAUAGGCUGUCACUCAUCAUGGACAUGGACAUCCCAGAUUCAUAGAUGACAUUCUUUGGAGCCAUUUGGUGAAGUGACAACAUAAUUUUUUGCAUAAUUUUUUCUAGCAAACUCUGAGAAUAAACUCACAGUUUAAAAAUAGCAAUAUGGUUUCCUCAGUUGAAUAAAACCAACUAAUGUAUAUGAUAAAGAAGAUAAAUUUUAAUUUUUCCUUUCAGAUUAAUGAUAUUUUACAUAAUAAAAUCUUUUUUUGCAUUACAAUUUUUCCAGCUAGAAAAAUUCAAAAAGAACUGUAACACUGCUGAAAUUAUUUUAAGAAAUGACAAUUAAAGUUUUCUUUUUGAUACAUCAUCACAGUCGGGCUGGUGGGAACUCCAUCUAGAUGGCUUGUCCAUCCUUUCAACAUUUAUUCCCUCUCCCCAAGAACUCCUGCAAACAUUUUAUUUUAUUUAAAAGAAUGUUCCAGGUCCACAUUUUUGGAGUAACCUGAGAAAGUCUUGUGCCCAAGUCACAAAGCAUGUAUUUCUUGCCAAGAGGCUUGAUUCAUUUGCUAGAGUACAGUGUUGGAGAUUAAAAACUCUGUGUAGAGAAGCAUUUUUCAUGGCCCUUCGUGAUGAGUCGGUCAUCACUGGGUACUCUGCAGAGGUAAAGAAAGUCUGUUGAAACUUAGGCGUUCACAUUGGCACUGUCAAUUUAGAGUUUCAUUCGCCGCAGAUAGCUAAAUCCUGCAGCCUAUCAUCAAUACCAUAGUAGUUUUUCUAUAGUUUUGACUAAAUGGUAAUAAAAGCAAAUUUAAUGACCUUUGUUUUAUCAGGUAACACAAUGUAAAUUCAAGCAAUGAUUAUAGGAUUUAUACAGUCAACAGGAGCCCCAGACAAGACACAGCCUUGGGCCAAACUGUAAAGUGUCCUGCUAAUGAGAUGCAGUCAGCUUUCUGUGGGGUUGACGCAGGUUUCCAACUGUAAGACAUUCUGGUCUGUUAAGAUCAUACAUGCACUGUCUGAUUUAUUCCUGGGUGAAUUUGCUGAAGUCAGUUUUAAUUAGAAGAUGUGUUUUGACUGACAGUUCUUGGUGUCUGUGUUCGGCUAGUGUUUCUUUCUUGGUAGAAACAUUUAGGUGCUGGAGUGCUAUUCUUUCUUAUCAGGAGGUAAAAAGGCAAUUUAAGUUCCAGAGUCAUGCUCAGGGGAUGGAUUCAGCCACACCCUGGCCUGCGGUGUGCAAGCUUCAAGUUGUUUUUGGCAAAUCCAUUUGACUUCCAUCCUGUCAGAUUAUGUAUUUUAGUGAUAUCCUUGGAAUCUACAGAUCGUUAAAGUGAGCUCUUUUGAAAAUGAGCACAAACAUGGGACACACUAUUCAUUUCCCUCAGUGUAAAGUUUCAGAGAAAAUGCAGAAACUCUCCUGUUCUUCUAGUUCACACCUUUAUGAGGGUCCCGUUUAACCUGUUUGCAAAUCCUUUUUCUUUUUUUUUCUUUUCUUUUUUUUUUGUGAGACAGAGUCUCACUCUGUUGCCCAGGCUGGAGUGCAGUGCUGACCAGACAGGGAUGUUGUUCGUAGGAGAUGCUGUUCUCCAGGUUAAUGGCAUACAUGUAGAAAAUGCAACUCAUGAAGAAGUGGUGCAUCUGCUGAGAAAUGCUGGCGAUGAAGUUACCAUCACCGUUGAGUAUCUCAGGGAAGCGCCGGCAUUUCUGAAGCUCCCGUUAGGGUCCCCAGGGCCAUCCAGCGACCACAGCAGUGGGGCCUCCUCUCCCCUCUUUGACAGCGGUUUGCAUCUGAACGGAAACUCCAGUACCACAGCCCCAUCGUCACCUUCCUCGCCCAUAGCUAAGGACCCGAGGUAUGAGAAGCGCUGGCUGGACACCUUGUCCGUGCCUCUGUCCAUGGCUCGCAUCUCAAGGUACAAAGCCGGAACGGAAAAAUUAAGGUGGAAUGCGUUCGAGGUGCUCGCCCUGGACGGAGUCAGCUCUGGGAUCCUCCGGUUUUACACAGCCCAGGAUGGCACCGACUGGCUGCGGGCGGUCUCAGCCAACAUCAGGGAGCUGACACUUCAGAACAUGAAGAUGGCGAACAAAUGCUGCUCUCCUUCCGACCAGGUUGUGCAUAUGGGGUGGGUAAAUGAGAAACUCCAAGGAGCUGACUCCUCUCAAACCUUCAGACCCAAGUUCCUAGCACUGAAGGGCCCGUCCUUCUACGUUUUCAGCACUCCUCCGGUGAGCACAUUCGAUUGGGUGCGAGCAGAAAGGACCUAUCACCUCUGUGAGGUGCUAUUUAAAGUUCACAAGUUCUGGCUCACAGAGGACUGCUGGUUGCAAGCAAACUUGUAUCUGGGUCUUCAAGAUUUUGACUUUGAGGACCAGAGGCCCUAUUGCUUCAGCAUCGUGGCCGGCCAUGGGAAGAGCCAUGUUUUCAACGUGGAGCUUGGCAGCGAGCUGGCCAUGUGGGAGAAGUCCUUCCAAAGAGCCACGUUCAUGGAAGUUCAGAGAACCGGGUCCAGAACAUACAUGUGCAGCUGGCAAGGAGAGAUGCUGUGUUUCACGGUGGAUUUCGCGUUGGGAUUUACCUGUUUUGAGAGUAAGACCAAGAAUGUGCUCUGGAGAUUUAAAUUUUCCCAGCUUAAGGGAUCUUCAGAUGAUGGGAAAACUCGAGUAAAGCUGCUGUUUCAGAAUCUGGACACCAAACAGAUUGAGACGAAGGAACUCGAGUUCCAGGACCUGAGGGCUGUCCUGCACUGCAUCCACUCCUUCAUAGCAGCCAAGGUGGCCUCCGUGGACCCCGGCUUCAUGGACAGUCAGAGUCUUGCCAGAAAAUACAUGUACAGCAGCUAAAGGUUGUUUCUGUUGAGUGCUGAAAAAUUAAAUUAUUUUCGUAAGAAAUGAUUCUUUCCUGCAGAAUAUUGCAACUUUGUGUUGUUUUAUGAUGAGCCUAUAGUUGUGAUACCAAUAAAACAUGUCACUAGUUUCCAAA